AAGCACCGGACCAGGGGGAAGGCGAGCAGUGCCAAUCUACAGCGAAGAAAGUCUCGUUUGGUAAAAGCGAGAGGGGAAAGCCUGAGCAUGCAGAGUGUGCAGAGCACGAGCUUUUGUCUCCGAAAGCAGUGCCUUUGCCUGACCUUCCUGCUUCUCCAUCUCCUGGGACAGGUCGCUGCGACUCAGCGCUGCCCUCCCCAGUGCCCGGGCCGGUGCCCUGCGACGCCGCCGACCUGCGCCCCCGGGGUGCGCGCGGUGCUGGACGGCUGCUCAUGCUGUCUGGUGUGUGCCCGCCAGCGUGGCGAGAGCUGCUCAGAUCUGGAGCCAUGCGACGAGAGCAGUGGCCUCUACUGUGAUCGCAGCGCGGACCCCAGCAACCAGACUGGCAUCUGCACGGCGGUAGAGGGAGAUAACUGUGUGUUCGAUGGGGUCAUCUACCGCAGUGGAGAGAAAUUUCAGCCAAGCUGCAAAUUCCAGUGCACCUGCAGAGAUGGGCAGAUUGGCUGUGUGCCCCGCUGUCAGCUGGAUGUGCUACUGCCUGAGCCUAACUGCCCAGCUCCAAGAAAAGUUGAGGUGCCUGGAGAGUGCUGUGAAAAGUGGAUCUGUGGCCCAGAUGAGGAGGAUUCACUGGGAGGCCUUACCCUUGCAGCUUACAGGCCAGAAGCCACCCUAGGAGUAGAAGUCUCUGACUCAAGUGUCAACUGCAUUGAACAGACCACAGAGUGGACAGCAUGCUCCAAGAGCUGUGGUAUGGGGUUCUCCACCCGGGUCACCAAUAGGAACCGUCAAUGUGAGAUGCUGAAACAGACUCGGCUCUGCAUGGUGCGGCCCUGUGAACAAGAGCCAGAGCAGCCAACAGAUAAGAAAGGAAAAAAGUGUCUCCGCACCAAGAAGUCACUCAAAGCCAUCCACCUGCAGUUCAAGAACUGCACCAGCCUGCACACCUACAAGCCCAGGUUCUGUGGGGUCUGCAGUGAUGGCCGCUGCUGCACUCCCCACAAUACCAAAACCAUCCAGGCAGAGUUUCAGUGCUCCCCAGGGCAAAUAGUCAAGAAGCCAGUGAUGGUCAUUGGGACCUGCACCUGUCACACCAACUGUCCUAAGAACAAUGAGGCCUUCCUCCAGGAGCUGGAGCUGAAGACUACCAGAGGGAAAAUGUAACCUGUCACUCAAGAAGCACACCUACAGAGCACCUGUAGCUGCUGCGCCACCCACCAUCAAAGGAAUAUAAGAAAAGUAAUGAAGAAUCACGAUUUCAUCCUUGAAUCCUAUGUAUUUUCCUAAUGUGAUCAUAUGAGGACCUUUAUAUCUGUCUUUUAUUUAACAAAAAAUGUAAUUAACUGUAAACUUGGAAUCAAGGUAAGCUCAGGAUAUGGCUUAGGAAUGACUUACUUUCCUGUGGUUUUAUUACAAAUGCAAAUUUCUAUAAAUUUAAGAAAACAAGUAUAUAAUUUACUUUGUAGACUGUUUCACAUUGCACUCAUCAUAUUUUGUUGUGCACUAGUGCAAUUCCAAGAAAAUAUCACUGUAAUGAGUCAGUGAAGUCUAGAAUCAUACUUAACAUUUCAUUGUACAAGUAUUACAACCAUAUAUUGAGGUUCAUUGGGAAGAUUCUCUAUUGGCUCCCUUUUUGGGUAAACCAGCUCUGAACUUCCAAGCUCCAAAUCCAAGGAAACAUGCAGCUCUUCAACAUGACAUCCAGAGAUGACUAUUACUUUUCUGUUUAGUUUUACACUAGGAAACGUGUUGUAUCUACAGUAAUGAAAUGUUUACUAAGUGGACUGGUGUCAUAAACUUUCUCCAUUUAAGACACAUUGACUCCUUUCCAAUAGAAAGAAACUAAACAGAAAACUCCCAAUACAAAGAUGACUGGUCCCUCAUAGCCCUCAGACAUUUAUAUAUUGGAAGCUGCUGAGGCCCCCAAGUUUUUUAAUUAAGCAGAAACAGCAUAUUAGCAGGGAUUCUCUCAUCUAACUGAUGAGUAAACUGAGGCCCAAAGCACUUGCUUACAUCCUCUGAUAGCUGUUUCAAAUGUGCAUUUUGUGGAAUUUUGAGAAAAAUAGAGCAAAAUCAACAUGACUGGUGGUGAGAGACCACACAUUUUAUGAGAGUUUGGAAUUAUUGUAGACAUGCCCAAAACUUAUCCUUGGGCCAUAAUUAUGAAAACUCAUGAUCAAGAUAUAUGUGUAUACAUACAUGUAUCUGGUUUGUCAGGCUACAAGGUAGGCUGCAAAAUUAAAUCUAGACAUUCUUUUAAUGCCACCACACGUGUUCCGCUUCUCUCUUUUAAAGUAUUUAUAAAAAUAUAAAUUGUACAUUUUGUAAAAUAUUAUGUUUGAUUUCUCUACUUGUCAUAUCACUAAAUAAACACGAUUUUAUUGCUGCGUGACUCUGUAUUACUUUGGUGCAUAAAAGUUGAACAUUGUUGUUUACUGAAAAUAAAAUUAAAAUUUAUGAAUUAAA